CUUUUCCCUCCAUGGUUUCUCUCCGCUCCCGUGAGUAACUUGGCUCCGGGGGCUCCGCUCGCCUGCCCGCACGCCGCCCGCCACCCAGGACCGCGCCGCCGGCCUCCGCCGCUAGCAAACCCUUCCGACGGCCCUCGCUGCGCAAGCCGGGACGCCUCUCCCCCCUCCGCCCCCGCCGCGGAAAGUUAAGUUUGAAGAGGGGGGAAGAGGGGAACAUGGACAUGAAGAGGAGGAUCCACCUGGAGCUGAGGAACCGGACCCCGGCAGCUGUUCGAGAACUUGUCUUGGACAAUUGCAAAUCAAAUGAUGGAAAAAUUGAGGGCUUAACAGCUGAAUUUGUGAACUUAGAGUUCCUCAGUUUAAUAAAUGUAGGCUUGAUCUCAGUUUCAAAUCUCCCCAAGCUGCCUAAAUUGAAAAAGCUUGAACUCAGUGAAAAUAGAAUCUUUGGAGGUCUGGACAUGUUAGCUGAAAAACUUCCAAAUCUCACACAUCUAAACUUAAGUGGAAAUAAACUGAAAGAUAUCAGCACCUUGGAACCUUUGAAAAAGUUAGAAUGUCUGAAAAGCCUGGACCUCUUUAACUGUGAGGUUACCAACCUGAAUGACUACCGAGAGAGUGUCUUCAAGCUCCUGCCCCAGCUUACCUACUUGGAUGGCUAUGACCGAGAGGACCAGGAAGCACCUGACUCAGAUGCCGAGGUGGAUGGUGUGGAUGAAGAGGAGGAGGACGAAGAAGGAGAAGAUGAGGAAGACGAGGACGAUGAGGAUGGUGAAGAAGAGGAGUUUGAUGAAGAAGAUGAUGAAGAUGAAGAUGUAGAAGGGGAUGAGGACGACGAUGAAGUCAGUGAGGAGGAAGAAGAAUUUGGACUUGAUGAAGAAGAUGAAGAUGAGGAUGAGGAUGAAGAGGAGGAAGAAGGUGGGAAAGGUGAAAAGAGGAAGAGAGAAACAGAUGAUGAAGGAGAAGAUGAUUAAGACCCCAGAUGACCUGCAGAAACAGAACUGUUCAGUAUUGGUUGGACUGCUCAUGGAUUUUGUAGCUGUUUAAAAAAAAAAAAAAGGUAGCUGUGAUACAAACCCCAGGACACCCACCCACCCAAAGAGCCAAAGAAUAGUUCCUGUGACAUUCCGCCUUCCUUCCAUGUAGUCCCUCUUGGUAAUCUACCACCAAGCUUGUGGACUUCACCCCAACAAAAUUGUAAGCGUUGUUAGGUUUUUGUGUAAGAUUCUUGCUGUAGCGUGGAUAGCUGUGAUUGGUGAGUCAACCGUCUGUGGCUACCAGUUACACUGAGAUUGUAACAGCAUUUUUACUUUCUGUACAACAAAAAAGCUUUGUAAAUAAAAUCUUAACAUUUUGGGUCUGUUUUUUCAUGCUUUGCUUUUUAAUUAUUAUUAUUAUUUUUUUUACAUUAGGACAUUUUAUGUGACAACUGCCAAAAAAGUAUUUUUAAGAAUUUAAGCGAAAUAAACAGUUACUCUUUGGUAAA